GCGGCGGCGCAGGACGUUCUCCCGCCGGGAGGACCACGCGGCGGUCCCUGGACCCUUCCCCGGGUGCACAGCGGCGGCUGCGCCAGCGGGGGCAGGAUGGGCCGUCCGAGCGCACCUCCAUCCGCCCUCGCGACGCCCACGCUGGCCCAGACGCGGGAUUUGGGGUGGAGGACGCUGGGCUGGGAACCAGCACCUUGGGACGGCCGGGUAGUUCGGGCCUUGAGGAGUCCCACACCCUGACAGCUGGCGCCCCCCACGCCCCGCCUAGCUCUCCUCGGCCUGGGGACACCGGCUGCCAGGCCUCUCCAGUUUCAGCCUUUCCUGGGAGGACUUCCUGGAAGAGGGGGCUUCAGGCCCCAGAAAGAGAGGCUGCUCUGGGGGAUGGAGGAGGUGCUGGGAUGGUGACUCCGCGGAGUCGAGGGUGUGAGGCGGGAUGUGGGCAGGCCGUGAGGUUUGUGUUGCAAGACUGGGAGGCAGGAUGAGGGGAGGCCAUGGGGCGGCUGGAGGUGCGGCCUGGGAGCCCUGCGUGCUGGGCCCUGGGCAGGGACGGCAGGCGAGGCGUGUGGAGGAAGAGCCGCGAAGAGCUGGGCGCUGUCUUCUCCACGCCUCCGUUUCUUCAUCUGCUCCUGGGGCCGCCUGCCCGGUAGCGGAGAUUGAAUCGCAUGUUGACGUCUAUUACGAUGAUUAAUGUUCUUGUCAUUCCCGUCACUAGCAGGUCCGGACAGGCCGAGAUGACGCCGAGCCCCCUGUUGCUGCUCCUGCUGCCGCCGCUGCUGCUGGGGGCCUUCCCGCCGGCCGCCGCCGCCCGAGGCCCCCCAAAGAUGGCGGACAAGGUGGUCCCACGGCAGGUGGCCCGGCUGGGCCGCACUGUGCGGCUGCAGUGCCCAGUGGAGGGGGACCCGCCGCCGCUGACCAUGUGGACCAAGGAUGGCCGCACCAUCCACAGCGGCUGGAGCCGCUUCCGCGUGCUGCCGCAGGGGCUGAAGGUGAAGCAGGUGGAGCGGGAGGAUGCCGGCGUGUACGUGUGCAAGGCCACCAACGGCUUCGGCAGCCUGAGCGUCAACUACACCCUCGUCGUGCUGGAUGACAUUAGCCCAGGGAAGGAGAGCCUGGGGCCCGACAGCUCCUCUGGGGGUCAAGAGGACCCCGCCAGCCAGCAGUGGGCACGACCGCGCUUCACACAGCCCUCCAAGAUGAGGCGCCGGGUGAUCGCACGGCCCGUGGGUAGCUCCGUGCGGCUCAAGUGCGUGGCCAGCGGGCACCCUCGGCCCGACAUCACGUGGAUGAAGGACGACCAGGCCUUGACGCGCCCAGAGGCCGCUGAGCCCAGGAAGAAGAAGUGGACACUGAGCCUGAAGAACCUGCGGCCGGAGGACAGCGGCAAAUACACCUGCCGCGUGUCGAACCGCGCGGGCGCCAUCAACGCCACCUACAAGGUGGAUGUGAUCCAGCGGACCCGUUCCAAGCCCGUGCUCACAGGCACGCACCCCGUGAACACGACGGUGGACUUCGGGGGGACCACGUCCUUCCAGUGCAAGGUGCGCAGCGACGUGAAGCCGGUGAUCCAGUGGCUGAAGCGCGUGGAGUACGGCGCCGAGGGCCGCCACAACUCCACCAUCGAUGUGGGCGGCCAGAAGUUUGUGGUGCUGCCCACGGGUGACGUGUGGUCGCGGCCCGACGGCUCCUACCUCAAUAAGCUGCUCAUCACCCGUGCCCGCCAGGACGAUGCGGGCAUGUACAUCUGCCUUGGCGCCAACACCAUGGGCUACAGCUUCCGCAGCGCCUUCCUCACCGUGCUGCCAGACCCAAAACCGCCAGGGCCACCUGUGGCCUCCUCGUCCUCGGCCACUAGCCUGCCGUGGCCCGUGGUCAUCGGCAUCCCAGCCGGCGCUGUCUUCAUCCUGGGCACCCUGCUCCUGUGGCUUUGCCAGGCCCAGAAGAAGCCGUGCACCCCCGCGCCUGCCCCUCCCCUGCCUGGGCACCGCCCGCCGGGGACGGCCCGCGACCGCAGCGGAGACAAGGACCUUCCCUCGUUGGCCGCCCUCAGCGCUGGCCCUGGUGUGGGGCUGUGUGAGGAGCAUGGGUCUCCGGCAGCCCCCCAGCACUUACUGGGCCCAGGCCCAGUUGCUGGCCCUAAGUUGUACCCCAAACUCUACACAGACAUCCACACACACACACACACACACUCUCACACACACUCACACGUGGAGGGCAAGGUCCACCAGCACAUCCACUAUCAGUGCUAGACGGCACCGUAUCUGCAGUGGGCACGGGGGGGCCGGCCAGACAGGCAGACUGGGAGGAUGGAGGACGGAGCUGCAGACGAAGGCAGGGGACCCAUGGCGAGGAGGAAUGGCCAGCACCCCAGGCAGUCUGUGUGUGAGGCAUAGCCCCUGGACACACACACACAGACACACACACUGCCUGGAUGCAUGUAUGCACACACAUGCGCGCACACGUGCUCCCUGAAGGCACACGUACGCACACACGCACAUGCACAGAUAUGCCGCCUGGGCACACAGAUAAGCUGCCCAAAUGCACGCACACGCACAGAGACAUGCCAGAACAUACAAGGACAUGCUGCCUGAACAUACACACGCACACCCAUGCGCAGAUGUGCUGCCUGGACACACACACACACACGGAUAUGCUGUCUGGACGCACACACGUGCAGAUAUGGUAUCCGGACACACACGUGCACAGAUAUGCUGCCUGGACACACAGAUAAUGCUGCCUUGACACACACAUGCACGGAUAUUGCCUGGACACACACACACACACGUGUGCACAGAUAUGCUGUCUGGACACGCACACACAUGCAGAUAUGCUGCCUGGACACACACUUCCAGACACACGUGCACAGGCGCAGAUAUGCUGCCUGGACACACGCAGAUAUGCUGUCUAGUCACACACACACGCAGACAUGCUGUCCGGACACACACACGCAUGCACAGAUAUGCUGUCCGGACACACACACGCACGCAGAUAUGCUGCCUGGACACACACACAGAUAAUGCUGCCUCAACACUCACACACGUGCAGAUAUUGCCUGGACACACACAUGUGCACAGAUAUGCUGUCUGGACAUGCACACACGUGCAGAUAUGCUGUCCGGAUACACACGCACGCACACAUGCAGAUAUGCUGCCUGGGCACACACUUCCGGACACACAUGCACACACAGGUGCAGAUAUGCUGCCUGGACACACGCAGACUGACGUGCUUUUGGGAGGGUGUGCCGUGAAGCCUGCAGUACGUGUGCCGUGAGGCUCAUAGUUGAUGAGGGACUUUCCCUGCUCCACCGUCACUCCCCCAACUCUGCCCGCCUCUGUCCCCGCCUCAGUCCCCGCCUCCAUCCCCGCCUCUGUCCCCUGGCCUUGGCGGCUAUUUUUGCCACCUGCCUUGGGUGCCCAGGAGUCCCCUACUGCUGUGGGCUGGGGUUGGGGGCACAGCAGCCCCAAGCCUGAGAGGCUGGAGCCCAUGGCUAGUGGCUCAUCCCCACUGCAUUCUCCCCCUGACACAGAGAAGGGGCCUUGGUAUUUAUAUUUAAGAAAUGAAGAUAAUAUUAAUAAUGAUGGAAGGAAGACUGGGUUGCAGGGACUGUGGUCUCUCCUGGGGCCCGGGACCCGCCUGGUCUUUCAGCCAUGCUGAUGACCACACCCCGUCCAGGCCAGACACCACCCCCCACCCCACUGUCGUGGUGGCCCCAGAUCUCUGUAAUUUUAUGUAGAGUUUGAGCUGAAGCCCCGUAUAUUUAAUUUAUUUUGUUAAACAUGAAAGUGCAUCCUUUCCCUCCA